GGGCUUAAGGGAGCCUGGCUAGGCCGGCAGCCGGAUGGUCCCGCAGCUCGGGGCCGGCCAUGCUUCGCGGUCCGUGGCGCCAGCUUUGGCUCUUUUUCCUGCUGCUGCUCCCGGGCGCGCCUGAGCCCCGCGGCGCCUCCAGGCCGUGGGAGGGAACCGACGAGCCGGGCUCGGCCUGGGCCUGGCCGGGCUUCCAGCGCCUGCAGGAGCAGCUCAGGGCGGCGGGUGCCCUCUCCAAGCGGUACUGGACGCUCUUCAGCUGCCAGGUGUGGCCCGACGACUGUGACGAGGACGAGGAGGCAGCCACGGGGCCCCUGGGCUGGCGCCUUCCUCUGUUGGGCCAGCGGUACCUGGACCUCCUGACCACGUGGUACUGCAGCUUCAAAGACUGCUGCCCUAGAGGGGAUUGCAGAAUCUCCAACAACUUUACAGGCUUAGAGUGGGACCUGAAUGUGCGGCUGCAUGGCCAGCAUUUGGUCCAGCAGCUGGUCCUAAGAACAGUGAGGGGCUACUUAGAGACGCCCCAGCCAGAAAAGGCCCUUGCUCUGUCGUUCCACGGCUGGUCUGGCACAGGCAAGAACUUCGUGGCACGGAUGCUGGUGGAGAACCUGUAUCGGGACGGGCUGAUGAGUGACUGUGUCAGGAUGUUCAUCGCCACGUUCCACUUUCCUCACCCCAAAUAUGUGGACCUGUACAAGGAGCAGCUGAUGAGCCAGAUCCGGGAGACGCAGCAGCUCUGCCACCAGACCCUGUUCAUCUUCGAUGAAGCGGAGAAGCUGCACCCAGGGCUGCUGGAGGUCCUUGGGCCACACUUAGAACGCCGGGCCCCUGAGGGCCACAGGGCUGAGUCUCCAUGGACUAUCUUUCUGUUUCUCAGUAAUCUCAGGGGCGAUAUAAUCAAUGAGGUGGUCCUAAAGUUGCUCAAGGCUGGAUGGUCCCGGGAAGAAAUUACGAUGGAACACCUGGAGCCCCACCUCCAGGCGGAGAUUGUGGAGACCAUAGACAAUGGCUUUGGCCACAGCCGUCUUGUGAAGGAAAACCUGAUUGACUACUUCAUCCCCUUCCUGCCUUUGGAGUACCGUCACGUGAGGCUGUGUGCACGGGAUGCCUUCCUGAGCCAGGAGCUCCUGUAUAAAGAAGAGACACUGGAUGAAAUAGCCCAGAUGAUGGUGUAUGUCCCCAAGGAGGAACAACUCUUUUCUUCCCAGGGCUGCAAGUCUAUUUCCCAGAGGAUUAACUACUUCCUGUCAUGAAGGCUAGAGGAAGACUUCCUGGAACUGCCUUUCUUCCACUAACAGGACCCUGGGACCUGUAGGAGCACCCCGUUUGGGACUGUGAGGUGUUUGAGGGUGUGGACUGGCAUCCAGCAGCCACUAACAAACACACAACUGGUGUGUAAAAGGCAGGCCUUACAUUAGAAGCCAAGCCAAUCCUUUUUCUUUUUUUUGGAGGUCCCACCGAGAUAGAUAGGAACUUGGAUUGCUGAAUUCAAAAACAGAGCCCAUUCUUAAGAUCACUUGGUGCCUUAAAGACACGCAUUCCAAAGUGGAAUGUGGUUGAAGAAAGUGGGCCAGGUGGUUGAAGAAAGCCAUGUGGGAGCUCAGCAAAUCCCAAGGGCUUAUUAUGACACUCCAGAUGGUCUCCUUAGCAUCUCAGCUCUUCUGCAAGGAAGAGCUUGGGUGUUAGGCCUCAGAGGCUGUAGGGUCCUUGGGUUACAGAGCCGGGGAGAACGAAGUUCUGUGACCCAGGGGUGGAGAAUACACUCUAGGUUUGCAGGCUGGUGGGCUUUCAAAUUGGUACUUCCAGAGGAAAGCCAAGCUGCUUCUGUUGUGAGCGAAUCAGCCAAGAGCCUGAGGCUGAAGGGAAAAGUACACAGAGGAAGAUAUUUUACAAACCAGGUCAGUGUAGGCCAAGACUUAUGGUCUACAGAUUUUGGCGGGGGAGGGGGGACCUUUUCAAAGACAAUAGGGGGUCUUGACAUGUUUGUUGUAUGUAAAGAUGAUAAGAUUAAAAUUUUUGAUUUUCCUAAAA